AUUAUUAAAAGUGCCUCUCUUUCAUUAGCACAACUUACGUACAUUUUAACAUCUGAGAUGAGCAUUGUUUAUUUUAAUGGACUCUUUAAUAAUGCUUAUGUUAUGCCCUGAACUCUAGUUAGAAUGAAAAUGAGCAAGAACAACAAAAAUAAAUGGUGUUGGGGUUCGGCAGAGGAAAGAUGGGAGGAGUGCAUUAAGAGAGUGAAACCAAAAGAGAGGACAAAAAAUACAAUUUCUACUGUAGUUGCCUAAGAGCCUGUGCUUUUGUCCCUCUCUCUGAAUGUUUUAUUUUUGCUAUAAUUACAGCAUCUUGCCUGCACUUUGUCCCUCUGAUCCUUUGUUAAAGCCCAGAUCACUCUGUGCAGACUGCGCUUGUAGGUGUGAUUUAUUGAGUGACAAGUAGCUGUAGGGUAGAACACCCGCCUCUGUACCUGAGUAAAGUAUUAGACAUCACAGAGCUGGGGCAGGCAGGAGGGGGGCCGAGGAAGGAGUGGGGGAGGCGAAAAGCAAAGAGCAGUAACACAGCAGCUCCUGGAUACAGAUCAGACAAGAGGUUCUGCCACAAAUCACCUAGAAACAUGUCAGACGCUGCAUGUUUGUUGUUUUACACUGAGGGCACAGCCGUAGUCCAAAAGUAUUGAUUCUUUUCUUUGUACAGAGACAGAGACUGUCAGACCUAGCAGGCUGACCUUGGUAUGGUGCAGACAACUAUUCCCCACCCUGCCGACCAGAUGAACCCCACAGGAGCAGCCUAGGCAAGAUAUGCCAAUGUCCACUUCACAGGCACAGAGAGAAACCGAUGCCUGCUGAAACGGCUCCUUCUGUUUCCCAAACACUUCCCCCGCCAGGCCCCCAGAGUGCUCCUUGUGACAGAAAAUUGGAGGCAGGAUUCUUGGAGGGAGCGUGUGUGCUUUUUUGUGUGUGUCUUAAAACACACAAAAAGAAGCCCUUUUUAUUUCAUUUGUCCGUGAGAUAAACUGAAGGAUGUCUGGGCAAUGGUGUAUAUGUGUGCAUUUUGUAUUUAAGGCGGCAAGAGGAGAUAGUUUAUUUUCUGUUUGUACAUAUCGAAGGGGAGAUUUCUGUGUGUGGGCACUUACAUUUGUGAGUGCGUGUGUUUCCCCUCUUCUCUAUUUCAAAAGCUUUGGUGAGAUGGGGAAGAGUAAUCAACUGUCACACUUAAUUGAUCUGCAGUUAUUUUAAAAGUUGUUUAACAGUAAAACUACACAGACCCAUUUGUCCAUAUGAAUCUGCAGGUCUCUUUAUAGUCUUAAAAUUCACUGUACUCUUAAGUCAUUUUGCAGCAUUUAAAAAAUUCAUUUAUUCUGAAAAUCAGGUAAUUUUAAACUAAAAAUACUAGUUUGUAAUUUGGAGAUCAUCUAAUAUAAAUAGAAACAUAUAACCGCCAACAUUUUGAAAUCAAGAGUUCAAAACUUGAUCCCGUAAACCAUUAGGGAGUAGGGCCCACAGGGUGCCCUUGAGGAAGUAUACCCUAUCUCCUGUUGGGCUUGGUGUGUCAAGACUUCGGUUUGCCAGAAAUGCUUGCCUCCAAGUAGAAGGUGUUUCAGUUACUCUUUGCUGAAGCUGAGUGUUUUAUUUUGACUAACAAUAACAGGGAGGAUGCCUUUCUCCCUUUCACUUUUAGGAAUGUUGUUGCAUGCACAACUUCUGUCCAUAAGAUUGAGCUGUCCAUGAGGAAAAACUCCAGUAGAUUUCAGAUUUGCCCGAAGGAAAAUAUGAGGCACACUGAUGGGGAAGAAAAGUGAUGAUAUCAUGUGCACUUAGGGUGUAAAAACCUCUCCUUUAAAAACGAGGUUUCUCUUUUUCAAGUAAAAUAAUGCAGACAGGUUCAAUGUGUGUAAUACUAUAUUACAUUUGUAUAAUUCACUUUAAAUCUUUUAUUAAAGUGAAUUUUUCAAAAAGUAGACCACUGAAGAUAAAAAUAACAAGUAAGGCAUUCACUUUCGUGAAAAGCCCCAUUAUUUUCUACAUCUCCAUUUUCACAUUCAUCCUAUUUGUUUAAGUGACUGGUUUGGCAACCUAAAAGAAAACCCAAUGGUUAAAAAAAAACAUUUGUUUUAUAGUUAGUUUUUACUUGUUUUUAUAGUAUGAGAUCUCUGUGUAGUAUUGAGUUUUGCAGACUCCUGAGAGAAAAAAAAUUCUAAUAAAAGUGCUAUUAUCUGAAAACAAUGACUCAAUUAAUUAUUUUGGUUUCUUAUGUUGAUUCUAAAUAUUUCUUGUUUCUCUUUGUUGGGUCUUUAUGUCUCAUCCAAAACAGAUUUACAUUUUGAGGUUAGAAACAGCUGAACAAGUCUGCCUUUGGGUAUUAACAAAAUAAGCAAACUAUUUAGGAUAUAUCAAUGUCUUUACAAAAGGAUAUUCCACUUAUAAAAUGGGAGCUGAGGAACACAUAUGCUGUGUAAGAAAUACCAUCUAAGAAAAAUAAUGCAUAGAAUAGAUUAGGAAUGGUUUAAGAUCUGAACACUCAGGAUUGGUAUUUCUUAACACUCUAUUUUUUAUUUUAAUAUAUACAUGCUAAUCGUCUUUCUCUCUUCUCCGUAUAUGUUAUAGUCACUUGAUUUACUACUGAAAUUAUAUUGCUUUUGAAAGUGUCAGUUGAGUUAUCCCUUGCCUUGUUAGUAUCAUGUUUGAUUUCUUGGACAGAGACAUAAAUCACUAUCUCAUAUGCAGGUCUUUUGAAGACGCACCCAAGGUUUAUUGCCAGUAACAGACUAGUGGCCUUAUGUGGACUUUCCAUGAAUAAAACAGAUUGAUGAGCCAUUUUAUAGCAUCGCAAGCUGUAUUAUAAAUACAUCACCCUUUUCAGUAAUUUAACGUGAGGAACAGCCUAAUGAGCUCCCAGCCAUGAUCAGCCAGAGCUGGGAGUUUUGUUUAGCUUCUAGGACAAGUGACUGGUGGAGGGUAAGAAACCCAAACCCUGUAUUGUUUUCCCCAGUUCUGUGACAAAAUCUUGUAAUAUGAAUCAUUUGAAGUAAUAGUAAAGUAAAGAUGCAUUUAGAAUCUGUCAGAGUAAUAAAGGGAAAUGUAAAGUGGGUCUGAUUUUGCUUAUAGCUGAAAUCUAAGGUUAAGAUGAUAGGCUUUUUAAGUUACUUGUUUUUCUUUUACUGAUUGAAGUCAUCAAUUGAAUAAACAGAUUCUCAUUUUGAAAUAUACAUGAUGUAAUAUCUACCUGAUAGCUUGGAAAAGGAACAGGUAGAUAUAGUUACAACAUCGUAACGGUCUCUUUUGAAAGUAUAGCUUAAGAUGACCAUUGUUUCUGUAUUCAAGCCUUCUUUUUUGCAUAGCUUACAACACUUUACCUUUAUUUUUUCAUUAAUCCUUAAAAUAUCCCUGUGGAAUAGGAUGAGUGGGUGGCAUCUUAGGGUAAACAGUUACUAUCCUUUCUGGUGAGGAAACCGAGGCAUAUAGAAAUGGUUGUUUUUAAAGAGUUAUCUGACUAGAAAGAAAAGCAAGAUAAAAUUAAUUUUUAGAAGUGAAAAAUAUUUUGCAUUACGUAUAGCACAUGUCAAUAUUUACAAAACUUACACAAACAUAACUUUGUGGACCUAUAAUUUUCUAAAAGUUUGGAAAGUAGGCGACACUUAGGAUUGGAAAAGGCAUAGCUUUGUGAAUAAUUUUUUUGCUACCUGGAAGCUGCAAUAUAUUUUGAGCUAGAAGCUUCUAUAAGAUAUUUCCCUUUUCUGAAUGCAAUUGAUUAUGCUAUACUGCAUAAUACUACAUUUACCUAUAUAUAAUCCAGUUAAAGCUGUAUUACAUAUUUAUAGAAGUCAGACUUUGGUCUGAAAUGCCAUUAUUUAUAAACACAAAUCAGUGAGUAAUUAGUCUACUGUGUAAAAAAAAUAAAAAAAAAUUUUGAAAUAAUCUUUUCUACUGUGAAAACAGCCAGGCAGUUUGGUGGACUCUGUUAUUCAUAUGUCAGACGGGAAUUACCUUGAGUGUACAGGGAAGAAUGAAGAACUGAAAAGGCUUUAAUUUUCUUUAAAGAAUAGGUAAAAACAGAAUAUUUUACCACUAAGGCAUGAACACAUCAGUGAUGCCCUAACCAGUUGAGCUCAGUCCUGCCUACACUGAGACACAAUGCACUUUCAAUUUAAAAAUACAUCUAAUUUAAAUGGAAUGGUCCUAUUUAUGCCCUCUGUUCCUUAUUAAAAAUGGUCGACAAGUAAAAUUCCGUUUAAGAAUACCUGCAGACAGUCAAUAUUGUUUUGAAUUUUAAAGAGUUCCUGUGUCUUGUGAAUGACAUUAUGCCUUUAAUAUUCCGUAUUCAGGGCAGAGUCCUUUUGAAACCAACUGUGCAUUUAUCUCCAUUUUUGCUUUCUUGGUCUUUGCCUUCCUCUGCCAUGCACCCAGGGUUGAGUGCUGACUGCAGGUCUAAGCUUAUCAGAUUGGAUGAACCUCUUCGGUGUCUCCAUUUUGGAAACUGUGGGUGAGAAUUUAAUGUUCCCCUAGCCCACACUUUGAAAAUGCAAGAUUACAGAAGAUUUAUGAAGGCCUCUGUGUCUCCAUAGCUCUGUUCUUUGGGGUACCUCUGAAGUUUACUACUGAGCGAAUGAUCUUGGCAUGUUAGUAUAGGCUGAGCCAAAGUUUGUGCUAUAUUAUUUAUGAUUCUAUAGCAUUGGCCUCUCAAACAAAUGAAGUUUAUUGACGUAUCAUCUGGAACAAAAUUUUGGCUAAUUCAUAAUUUAUACAUCAGAAAUAGAUGCCUUUCUCUUAUAGAUUGUGCCACUUGAACAUAAAAUAAGAUUUUAAGAUUAAAAGAAACAGAGGCCUGUAGAAGUGGCUUUUCAAGCUUGUAGUCACUGAUGGUUUUUUAAUCCCUAAACAACACAAAACAAAGGAAGACAGAAUAUGCUUUUCCCUCUCCCAUACUUCCCUUUUCUGUCUCUAAUUGUAAGCUCUUGUGCACCAGUGCUCCUACUUUUCCUCUGAGUUUAGUGAUAGUUCAUAAGAAAAGCAUUAGGCUUAUGGAAAGAAAGAUCUGUCGCCAGUGGACUUGAUUCUCCCUUGUGAUUUAUAAGGGUCUGAGAAAGCAGUCUUCCAGGUCUUCUCUUCUCAAGGACUCUGGGAAAGUCUUGUUCAAAACUAAUGGUUCUUAAAGAAUUGGUCAGCUGCAGACCACUGGCCUCUCAAAACACUGGGUGGUUCAGGUGGAUAGCACACACUGCUUUGCAACUCCAAGAUGCAGUGGGUGUGCUGGGGCCCGUGAGUCCGUCCUGGAAGACCUUUGGAAAUUCUGUGUUAGUCAGGCUCAUUCUCUUUCACUUGAUGUGCGCACAGAUUUUUGUAGAAAUCAUUUGAUAUCCCAGUAGUGUACAAAGCAUGGGAUGAUAUAUGCAUUCACACACUUACAUAUCAAAGAUACACUUCUUCUAUGUUUUUGUCUUUCAUACAGAGUCUAAGGCGACUAAGUCGUUAUGCUAUUUUAGCACAUAAAGAUAUCAUUGGUUUUAACUCAAAGUGAUUGACUCAAACUAUAUUUUUAUCAUAGUUUGAGUACCUCAUACUUGUUCACUGCCCUUAUGUGCAUGGUCACCUUUAGAGGGCAUAAUUCUGCUAAAAAACUAUUCCUAAUGAAUUGCAAAUGGAGAUGAGUUAAGUAAGCUGUGUUAAUUAUGUCAUUUGCAAGAUUGUCUAAUGUGGAAUUGGUCAAGAGACUGGAAACUGCUUGUCAAAUGUUUCUCUUAACUAAUGUGAUAGUUUGUGGUUUGCAGGUGACACAAUUUCCAUAACUUAUUUGAUGGAGCCUCAUUAACCACCCCUUAGUUCGCCUUAGCAAAAUUAUGUUAUUAAACAUGUCAUGAUAAGUUCUGUCCUCAUUACUUUGCAUUCGGCACAGUGAAUAGUGUUUGUCUUGUGACACCUCUCCCAGGUCCUUAGUCUUCGAGGAAGCCAAAGGAAUUCCAUGUUCAGAAUUGUGUUUUUAAGCUGCUUUCCAGCAUUACACACAUCUCUCUUGACUUGGCUAAUAGAACCUGGAUGUGUUCUCAAUCACUGCUAUCACCAUGCAGUCCUUAUUUAGCCCUCUGUCAUUUCUCCUCAGAGCUUGGUGUCCUGAUGUUCUACUGUCUUAAAUAGAAACCCAAAGAAUCUCUGAACCAUAUAGUUUUAGUUAAAAACAGCCAAGUGUAUGGCAGUAGUAACUGUGAUGAUAAUUCCAGUAGUGGAGCAGUUUUCGUUUUUCAUAGCAUCUGCCUCAUCUAGGAAAUCUUCACAUUAGCAGCAGAGCAUUUAUCUCUCUAGUGAAUAAUUUUUAUGUUUGCCCAUGUUUGUUGCUUAGUGCUGAGAAACUUCAUAUGUCUUUUUUUAAACACACACACACACAUAUUUUAUUGCGUACAUUGGUGACUCUCUGUAAUUUUGUCUUCAAAGGGACCAGUCUCAGAGAUACUUUACAGUGAUUGCCUUUUAGUAUUUAGUUUCUGUCACUUAAUUUUUUCUGGUGGUGGGAAUUCAUUUUUGUUAAUGUAUAAAAUUUUUCAAAAUUGGGAGAUGGUUGAAUAAGAUUAGAAAUAUAGUUCAUGGCAGUGGAAUAGACUAGCUAAUCCACAAGUGAACUGGAAUAGCAUAUUGAUCUAAAUGUAUAAGAUACCUUUAUUAAACCUGCCUAAGAGGAUCAUAUUUAAUAUUUAUUUUCUAGUGAGCAGUAUUGUACUUACUAAAUUGAUGGGAAUACACAUAUUGAUGAAUCUCUUAUAUUUUACUUGAAAAAUUCUGUUGAAGGCUACUUUAUCCUUUAACCUGAUAAACCCUCUCUCUCCCUCAUUCUCAAAAAUCUCAUCAUGGUUGCACUUGGAUCAAGCUUCUUCAUAAAGUCAUUGUCAUCUUACACUUUUCCCAGAAGCGUCACCCUAGGGGAAAAAUGAUUGUGUAAUAGAAAAACUCUCUCUGCAUUCUAUGCAUUGACCAUUCAUUAUCUUCCAUUUGGCUACCCUUUGACCUCCUUUCCCUGAGCCACAUAGCUAACCAGGUCGGCCUCUGUCAAAGUCUGUCUAAGGAUGUUAUUCUUCCUGUGGUCUCCCUUUUUCUUUCUACCUUCUACCGGCCCCCACCCGUACCACACACAUUCCGCCAAUUCUCUGUGCAGACUUGACAUAAGAUUCCACCCCAAUCCUUGUUAUGUAACCUACCACCUACCCCUUUUUGGCAAGGGACACCCGAGUCAGCAAGUUGCAACAAAGAGUGGAGUUAAUUGGAACAUGUGCUGUGCCCAAAUCUCAACAAAGAAGGGCUGAUAGACAUCAGGAAAACACAACCAUAUGUAGAUGUUUGCUUGAGGAAUAUGAGUGUACAUGGGAAAUAUCAUCUACAACCAGGUUGCAUUUAAAUAAAAUCAACCAUCAUUCUCCUCUUUGUCUUCCGACACCCCUUUCCCCCACAUGUAAUACUUUUAACUUGCUCUCUCAUGUCUGCUCAUGGGUGGGCAUGGUCUACUAAACUGACAAAUGAAACAGAUCUGUCUGUGAUACUUCAUAUGGGGAACCUUAUGUAACUUAUGCGGGGGACUCAGCUAUGGAUGACAUCCCAGUAGACCCUCUAUGGAUUCCCAGCUGUUACAAUAUCUCAUACCCUUUGUGACCUUUUCUUCUAUUUUUGCAUCCCUUUUAGAAAUUUAGGAUUUUUUUAAUUUAACCCCGAAUUUCUUAAAUGUGGGUACAAUUUACACAGAAUGAAAUAGACCCAUUUUAAGUGUACAGUUUAUGAGUUGUGACAAAAUGUGUAUACUCAUAUUAAACUAUCGCCCCAACCAAAGUACGUAUCAUUUUCUUUACCCCAUAAUGUUCCCUUAUGCCUUUUCCAGUUAAUCUCCUUUCCCCUAAGGCAACCAUUAUUUUGAUUUGUCACAAUAGAUUCAUUUUACCUGUUCAAGAACUUUAUAUAAAUUGGAUCAUACAGUAUGUACUAUGUUGUGUCUGGCUUUUUUUGUUUGUUUUUCUCAUAUUGUUGUGUGUAUUAGUAGUUUGUGUCUUCUUUAUUACCAAGUAGUAUUUCACUGUAAACAACAGCCAUUUAAAAAAUGAAUAUUUAGACAUAUUUUAUGAGUUGUUUCUAUAUAGUGGAGACAUCUUAAAAUUGCAGCAACUCUUGAGUUUAACAAAUAGUUGACUGUCAUCAGACUUUCACUUUUUUACUACUUCCCUGCCCAAGGGUGCUGGAAUUCCCCAGCUGUGGGCUGAAUGCCCAUCCCAAAUUCUCAGGCUUCUGGGUAUUCUUGGUUCACAUCCUGAACUUCAGAAGGAAUGGUGACCUCCAGUUCACUGAGAUGGUUUAGAACAUCUUAAAACUUUUGCUAUCCUCACUUACGUUGUGAAACUGUUUUGCUAACUGGAAGGUAGACGUGUUGCUGUGUACAAGUGAGGAUUCUGAAACAAUACGAAGGCCUUUUCAGAACCCUGUGGAAUGACCUGAAAGGAACUUUGUCUUUGAGCGUCUCCUGAUGUGUAUUUUCGAUAAUGUAUCCUGCCCUCAGUGUUUUUCUCUGUAGGUUUUAAAGGCCUCAGAAGUCCCAGAAUGGUUCUGGACCUGAGUUGCUACUUGAGAGGAUCUUGUAAUCCUGCUGGUCUCUAGAUACCUUUAGGACAGAAGUGCUGGGUGAUUAGGUUAAUAAUACUUAUUCUUUAUUAAACUAUUUAACCAUUAUAAGCAAUAUGCUAAGAAUUUAUGUACAUUAAUUUAUAUAUAAUCUAACAUCCUGUUUAUGUUAAUACUGUUAUUAUUCCCACUUGCUAGCUGAGGAAACUAAGCCUAAAUAACUUACCCAUGGUUAUACAACUCUUGUGCUGUGAUGGGACAAGGAUGUGAUUCCAGAUCUGACAUCCAGUCCCACCAACAUUCUAUUCUAAGUCCCACAAAUACUUUCUGGACAUCUCCUCCCAAGUAUAAAAUAGACAGUGUGGUAAUGUACAUGUGUUUAGUAUUGGGUAUAAAAUAUCCAGUGUAAUAUAAUUGUUAAGCUAUUGAAUAUUAUGAAAAGUAUAAAAAUGUGACGUGAACUGGAGCCUCUAACUGCAUUGAAUUCUUUUCAUUUAAGGGUCUUAGAACAUGUGAAAAGGCAGAAAAUAAUAAUUUUUUAUAAAGAAUAGUAGUAAGAACUGUUGUGCACAUUUUGAAGGUGAAGAUUUUGAGACAAGAUUCUUUAACUUUUCCACAGCAAUAUAGAGUUAGAAGAAACCUAGACUGUCUCCCUGUGCCUCUUCCUCUACUCUUUCAAAUCUUCUUUUUCUCUUAUCCAAGCCAAGGUUCAAGGAACAUUAUUAAUUGUUAUCUUUUUUACCUGCAAGUCAUAGACAAGGACUAGAGAAAUUCUUGUAUGUGUUAAGAGUUUACCUAAGAGACUAUUAUGACAGCAGUCAGGAAUGAUUUCUUUAAAGUAUGUAAAUGUAGCGUCUUCAUUAUGGCUUAGAUUUACAAUGCUGACGACUUUGUGAAGCAGAGAAAGUUGAAGAGUUAGGGGCUGCUUUACGAAGUGUACUUUGGAACAGUUUCUAGUUUCUUUCAAACUUUGAAUUGAAAGAGAAAAAGCAAAGUAAGUACCUAAAUCAGCACUAGCCAAAAGAAAAGAAAGAGAAAGAGAAAAGAAACCUGCACAAGGCAGCAGCUACUCUCCAUUGGGAAGCUCAUCCCCUCCUUGACAGUUGCUGGGCUGGCUGUGCAAUGUUUGAUAUGUGCUACUUAUUUACUGUCUUUCUGUUUCUCUCUUGAUGCUCUUAGACUGACACUGUGUUAACUGUCUUAUGCCACUGAUUACAUCUUUCCUUUCAUCUUUGUUAUGACUAGUUUAAAGGAUAAAUGGUGAUUUUCUAUAAACACAAUACAUAAGCUUAAAGAAAAAGAUGAACAUUUUAGAGAAUUUGGGAUUAUUCAGAAUCCCUAUGACUAUAAAUGACUUAGCAUAUCUAGAAUGCACCGAGUUGAUUUAUUUUUUUCUAUUAAUAGUCAUCAUGAUUAGAUAGUACCAGCUUUAAUUUUAAGUUUUGUUGCCUGUGAAGUUUAUUUUCAAUGCUCAAUACCAUCCAAGAGAGAAUCUUGUUUAAAAAUUUUAAUCAAAACAUAUUUAAGGUGCUUGGAACCUAAGGGAUCACUUGAUUCAACCUUGUCAUUUCUCUGUUCAUCUUGCAAUAACUUGAGGGGGCCACCUAAGGUUAUUCUAGAUAUCUAGAUUCUUUUCCUCUUCUUGCCCCUUGACUCCAUUGAUAAAUUGAGAAUGAAAAUAUCUCUCUGGAAUAUCUUUUGAUUUGGUAUGUAUAGGAAACUUUGAUAUCAUUGUAGAAAGGCAGAAUAGAAAUAAAAGAUAUUUCAAAGUCUUUUGAUGUAGGUUACCAUUUGUAAAUCUGUGAAUCUCUGCUUUGACUUCCUGAAAGGUUAUCAGAAAGCUCUUCUAAGGUUCUCUUGGGGUACUUAUUACAGGCGUAUAGGUGUAGCCCUACCCCAUUCCACACCUCCCAUAGGUUCUUCUGAAAGUUUAUGGUGUUAAGAGAACUCAAGAUUUUUAAAACUGGCUACUUGUUCCUAUUGUUCUUGAGGAAAAUUGUGCUGAAGACAGCUGUUUGAAGAUUUCUUUAAUAUAAAAUCUUUAAUCUUAAACCAUGCUGAGGAAGGUCAGUUUGGGGCAGAAAAAGAGCCAUGUAUUUGUCCCAUUUACUCCAGAAGAAGCUAAAAAUGAUUUUUGAAUAGCAGCUACCCUUAUAAGUACCAAGAAACAUCAGAUGUGAUUGCUGCUUUUCACAUGCUUAGAAUAUAAUUUCUCCAUAUUUUUUCAUGCAAAAAAAGCAAAGAAUUCUAGAAUUAAAAAUAAGAGGGACCUAAGAUCAUAUAUGGUGCAGCUCCUAAGAUGCUACACCAUAACCAGUGUAAAAGUUGAAUCUUUGCUGGAGGGGGCUAUGCGUGGAUAUUUUUUUCACUUUCCGUAGGUGAUUCAAAUGUAUAGCCAAGGUUGAAAACCAGGAAUGUGGAUUCCAGACCAGCCUUUCUUACUUAUGUUUGGGGUUGCUGAGACUUACAGAAAGUAAAAUUAUUCUGUGAGUAGAUAACUAAUUAUUUGAGACCCAAAUUCUGGUCUCCCAGAAUUUGGUACCUCAUUUUUUUUUUUUUUUUUGAGACAGAGUCUUGCUCUUUCACCCAGGCUGGAGUGCAUUGUCGUGAUCUUGGCUCACUGCAACCUCCACUUCCCAGGUUCAAGCGAUUCUCCUGCCUCAGCCUCCCGAGUAGCUGGGAUUAUAGGUACGCACCACCAUGCCCGGCUAACCUCAUACGUUUUAAUCCCAAAUUAAUGCCAGCUCUAUAUAGAAAAGACAGGUCUGUGAUCAUUAUUCAUCUGUGUAGUUUUCUUUCUACUGUGAUAAUCAUAGCUCAGUUUAGGGAGCACUUACUGUUGGCCUGGCACCAUGACAGCAGUUUUACAGGGUUACUUUCUUAAUUAAGUAUACUCAUAUUCUCGUUUCACAAAUGAGGAAACAGGCCCAAAGAGAAAGUAACUUGUCUACAUUUUUAGAGCAAGAGUAAGUGGAGGUGCUGGAAUUGGAACCCUGAUAGUUAGAUUCCAGAACUGUGACUCUUGAACUACUUAACUGUACCUUCUCCUAGAAGGAUUUGAUUAUUGCUUUUCAUUCCAAAACAAAGUUUUGUGUAGACUAUUUAAGCCAUAGGGACUGUAGACUGUAUUUUGAAAGCCAAAAUUAAGAAAACAAAAAAUGUGGCCCCAAGGCACUCACUGUUUUUCUUCCUUGAUUCUUGAAUCUUAAGACAGCAUGGGAUAUUAGUGAUGACAGUCUUCCUACUGCCAAAUGGACGCUUGGCCACUAGUUGUAGAUUUGCUUCAAAGAUUUUGUGUCCUCAGAAGUGAAAGAAAAAUUUUAGUGAGGCACAUGCUGUGGGAAGGGUGGUUUGGUCAGUGGUUUUGUAGUAUGGUUUGUGUUGUUUUCUCAGUGUGGAGAAAAUAAGGAAAGCUAUAUAGUAAGGAAGAAUAUGUUAAAAUAUGUACUCUACCUUUCAAAGAAGAGUCCAGGGUGAGUAGCAAUGCUAGUGCCACCUGAAAGAACUUUGGAGAUGUUUCUUAGGUCAGAAUGAAAAGCUGUUGCAGUAUUGCCUAAAAUAGAAUUUAUAAAACAGAACGCUAUUGAGACUUGUUAAUGUUUACAGAUACUGUUUUCUUUCUCCUUUUCCUUAAAAAAAUCCUUAUGUGCUCACUUUAAAGUAUAAAAGUAAACAACAAAACUUGUAUUAUAUUAGGUGUAAUUUCAAGGAUAACGAAGUGGAAGGAGCAUGUUGGCAAGGUAAUUUUCUAGUAUCAGGUGAGUGUUUUAGAAGAAGGGUCACUACUUAUUUUGGCUUAUAGAACAUGAUGGUAAAUCAGAUGAUAAAUGUUGCUUAAUAACUUGCUGCAUUGGGUGUUUACUGAAUUGCGAAGGAAAAAUCUUUAACCAGUACGUUAGUAGAUAUUUGCCUGUGACUUUUAAUUAAAUGUUAACAGCAAACAGAAAAAUGGCCAUUCCAUUAAAUAGCAUCAUCUUACAUGGUAUUUUGAUUAUUUCUUGGCAUCUUCCAAAAAAAGGGAAUUCUCAUGUGGGAAUGAUGGCUGUAGCUUAGAGAGAAAGAGAGUUUACAUAUUUGAUUACAUAUUUGAUACAUAUUUAACAUGGCCAUAUCUUUGUAUAUAUGCUUUAUUUCAUUUAAUCCAUAUGCCCCCAUUGAAAUGUAACAUUUAUUUGGACUAGAAGUUUUGGAAUCUUAGCUGGAACCACUGAUUUCAGACACUUAUGUGAUAGCAGGAUUGUUUAGUCCAAUAUGUAAUUUGCAUCCGAAUACUUUAUUAAUCUAGAAAUUUUUAGUGGUGAAAUUAAGUUAUCUUUUGAAACAGUCUAGCAAAUUAGACUAAACAAUCAGGAAAUUAAUUAAAUAGAGGCAACAGAUUGGGAUAGUAAACCUAUUUGUAAUAUUAAUAAUAGCUCACUUUAAAAUAUCUGAGAAAGUGCCUCAGCAAAUUUAUUUGGUGUAGAUUUUUGUGUUUCCCAGACAUGGGAAAGGGAAGGUUCUUGAAGGAGAGAAGAAAUGUCCCACUCAUCUGACCACUUCCUUUCUGUUAUAAUUUAAGAUCUUUUCCAUGAUUUUAUUUUAAUCUUCUCACUGACUUUUUCAAUGAUUUACAAUCUGAAGUAUUUUGAAAAAUUAUCAUACUGUGCAUACUGUACAUAGUGUGAUUACUUUUGUGCAGGGAUUUAAAAAAGUAAUCAGUGGUCUUUCUUUGAGAAUGAACUUUUCUGGUAAUGAUUUCUACAACAUAGAACAAAGCCUUCAUUCUUUGUAUUUUCCAGUAGUUACUUUAUCCAGUAAUUCUCAUGCAUUUCUCUGUGAGCAUUUCUAAGGUCUUGUUCUGAGGGUCCAAUUUCCUAUAUUCACAUCCUGGCACAUCUGUAAAUGCUCACAGUGAUGGUGUCUUAACUCUUUCUAGAGCUGUGAACGUACUGCUUCUUGAGUUCUUAGACACCUCUCUUUCUAAAGUAACAGGAUCCUAGUGUUAGUUUCACUGUAAGAACUGAAAUCCAGAACCUGGAUGUCCUGUGACCACAAGGGGCAGAGCCAGGUCUUGGUUGCAGCUGUUCUGAUGCCCAGUUUGGACUCUUCCCUAGCUAGUCUGUUAUGCUGCAAGCUGAAGUUUACAAAUUUGAUGCCUCCUGUUGGGGUAUUUCUGAAGGGUGUAUAGGGUUAUCAAACACUCUUAAAAUACAUGCCUAAGGUCAUGCUUAAUGUAUACGGCAAACCAUCCCUCACAGUUUCUUGCAUAAACUUGAAUAUGUUCUACAUGUUUUCUCAGCCUAAUAGAAUGACCGCUUAAUUGAGUUGUAUAAUUUGAAAUGUUGAAGUGCAAUAAGAACAGGAGGACUCUCUGCUUUCUUUGGAAACUAUUAACCAGUAAAUGAAAAUUUAGUUGAAAACUAGUAGUUAAUAAUUGCCAUUUUCUAACAUGAAAGGAUUUUAUCCCUCAUGUGUUUUGUUAAACAUUGUAAAAGUGUCAAAAUUAGCUGAACUCUCAUGUAUUUGUAUUUAAUAUAAUCUGUUUAGAUGAUCUGGAUAUGAAAUGUGAUAGGAAUGAUGGUUGUAGCUUAGAGAGAAAGAGAGAGAGAUUGAGACCCUCUCUGAAUAUUUGGUUUCUGGAUUUAAUCACCAAUGCACUUAUUUUAUUACUCUUGGCUUUUGUAGUCUGAGGACUUUGUUUUCUUCUUUUGCUUAAUUUUCUUAACCUGAAAUGUGACUUGGCAAAAUUAAGGACAGAGGUGUAUCAAAUUCUUUGCUAGUCUCUAUUUUUUUUUUUGUGAAGAAGAGAUUUGUAUUACUACGUUUUAUUUAUAAUCUUUAGAAGAGCUAUAAUAGAAAUGGGUUCAUAGAUCUGUAAAAAUCAAAAUCACUCUUAAAAAAUCCCUCAAGCUGUCUGUCACUAAUGGGGGAAAAAAUGUAAUCCACUUUGGAGAUUUUUUUUUUUAAUGAGACAGGGUCUCACUCUGUUGCCCAGGCUAGAAUGUAGUGGUGCGAUCAUAGCUCACUGAAGCCUUGAACUCCUGGGCUUACGCAGUCCUCCUGCUUCAGCCUUCCAAGUAGCUAGGAUGGUAGGCAUGCAUCACCACACCUGGCUAAGUAUUAAAAAAAAUUUUUGUAGAGAUGGAGGUCUUGCUGUGUUGCCGAGGCUGGUCUGAAACUCUUGGGCUCAAGCGGUCUUCCUGCCUCAGCCUCUCAAAGCACUGGGAUUACAGGCAUGAGCCAGUGUGCCUGACUUGAGAUUUUUUUUUUUCCUGUGUUUUCACAUGUGUUGUUGUAAGGUUCAUUUGGUUUUGUUGUUAUUGUUGUUAAUAAGGACAUAAAAAAAUUUGAUAUGAGAAUUAACGAAGAGGCACUAACAUAAAGAUAAUAGAAAAGAAUAUAGUGGUAGCAUUCAACAGUGGUGUAUUGAGAUUGCAAUUAUUUCUUAAAACUUGAAAUCAUUUUUGAAAUACAUAUGUUAGACCUAUGUCUACAGAAACAAACAUGCCAGACACUGAGCUUUUCUUCUUUCUAGAUGUUGGUAAUUAGUAAGCAAAUGCUAAAAUUUAAUAUUAGAAUAAAAUGACCAGAUUUUUUCCAUUGCUUAACAGAGACCAAUAACAACAUUGUUAUGAAUAUAAAUUUUCAUUAUUUCUGUUAUUGAACUAAAAUUUGGUUUUGAUAAAAUGUCUCCUAAAGUGUCAUCCAAGAAUACUUUAUUAACUUCUGUUUUUAAAAAAUAAGUACAGUAAUUUUUUUGAUAACCUCAAACUUAUUAAGUUCACAUUAAGGAAAAGUUUCUUUUGAGGGAAAAUAGCCUAUUACACAUGACAUCCUUUUUCUUCUUAUGAGAGUUUCUUAAACCUUGGACUUUUAGAAUGUAUUUUCAAAUCAAUAAUAAUUGAAUCAUUAUUCUUACAUUACAUUGCUAUGCUAGACAUUAUUACUUUCUAAUUAUUAUCUUUAACUUUUGCAAUUUAUAUUAUCAUUGUGUUUAGAUGUUACAUUCCCUACUGAGAAUCAUAAAUCCUAUCCAGUGGUUUUAAGUGAGGCAAUUUAUGUGCGUUUAGAAAGAGACUCAAUUUUACUCAUUUAAAAUAAAUGGAGAGAAGGAAACAUUAAAAAUAGUAUUAUCGUACUCUAUUUGUAGUUUGCCAUUUUCUGUUUAGUGUAUUUUCGUAGAUGAAGGUUUUUUUUUCUUUUAAAGGUUGUCUAUCUCUAGGACUAUAGUUUUAUGAGUGGAAUGUCACAUAAUGCAUGAUAACAUAACCUAUAUGUAAGGGUUUUACAGGUAAUUAGAGCCAUACAGGCCAUUUGAGGGGUACAGGGGAGAACCUGAGCCUGAAGAAUCAUGUGUAGGAAAAAUCCUUGUAAUCUUAAGACUUUUUUUGGGUGUUUAACUUACUAAAAUGUCUUAAUUAUUAAACUUUCUUAAUGCUGGACAGUUAGGAGAAUAUUAAAAAAUAUAAAAUUAUUUUUAUCCAAGUUUUCUGUUUUAUCCAGUAAUCAGUAAUGAUCUGCCUUGAUUCUUCAAAGUACUAUUGAUGAAUUUCAUUUGAGUUGAUUUAGAAACAACUUUGUUGAUGAAAAGUUUGCUUAUGUAUGUAUUUUCAACAUUUUUAUGUCUAUGCACUUGGUUUCAGAUGAGAUAGGAAAUGGAAAUAACAAAACACUGUUAGAAAAUCUUGUUUCUGUAGACGGCUCAACCUUGCCAGAAACCACGAGGCAGUGGAAAUAUCACGAGAAAGCUUGUUCCUACAAGACUCCCAGACUGAUUACCAGACCAAAGAAGUUCCCAGAAAUUUAGCUUGAAGCAAUCAUUUAAAAUUUAGGAGGCGGAUCCAAUCCUGCUCGGAGUCAUCCAUUGCUAAUUAUAGUUGCCUAUGAUGUCCCAGUGAUUUUGUUAUCAGCCACACCUAAGUAUAUUUCUGAUUUUUUGCAUGUUCCCUCCAAAAUAUAUUCUUGCUGGGCACUUAAAAUCUGUUUAUUUCACUGUAUGUAUAUUACACCACAAUACUGUUCGCAUUUUGAAUCUAUGCAUUUUUUUUUCUUUGCCUGAUAUAUCUUGUUCAACCUUGAUGAGACAGAUGGCUUUUUUUCUUUUAAUCUAGUUUCAUUUGUAUCUUAAAAUUUCUAGUAGCUGGGGCACUCUCCUCACCCAGGUGAGGCCUGCUUUGCCCUACAGGUGUGUUAGAUGCAUGGUUGUGUGUACACAUCUUUGAAAUACAUGAGGCUGCUGCCUUUUAGAAAAGUUACUGUUUUUGCUUUUUUUUAAAUAAAUAUUUUGGCCAGCCUCAGAAAUUUAGUAAUGGCUUUGAACACUUGGAAUUAGCAUGAUAAAGCCAGAGUUUAUUAUAUACUGUUGUGAUUUAAAUCACACACUGGUUAUUUUGGGGAGUUAGAGCAAUCUACUUGACACAGACAGGUCUUCCCUGGCGGAGGCUUGCCCCUGCAUGUUCUGGAUAGAUGGCUUUGAUGUUGGGUGAACAUCACAACUUGAACUGCUGUGUUUACACUGUAAGAAUGCUUGCUGAAUCUCUCACUGCAUCUCUCACAUAAUUCCAACUUCACUUUAGUUCUGAAUACAUGAACAGUAAAGGGGGCAGUUUGCUUUUAAAUUUUGCUUGUCAGUUAGGCACUUUAAGAGUCUUAUUUCUUUAUGUGAUUUCCUGUAAGAGCUCAUAUAUGGGGAUUGUUAUUGAGUAAUUUUGAACACAAAAUUAAUUCUAUACCCUUUGAUGUGGCUAAUAAAAGCCAUAAGGGUAUGGUAGGAAAAGAAGAUAAGAAGAUAGAGAAAAAAAAAUUGCCUCUUUCUAUAUGGCAAGAAGAAGAAAAAAAAAAUUAAGAGCAGUUGUCUUUGAACCACAGCAGGGUUUACUCUUAAGGGUCUUCUAGCUUGUUUUUCCCAUUAGCUAGGAAAGCACUAUGUGAGCUUUAAAAAAAAAAUACAUAUAUAUAUAUAUUUAAAUCAUGGAAUAAUAUAGGACAAAUGAUUUAAAUUGAAUCUAGAUUUUGCAUGAACACUCUUCUAGUUUAUUGGUUAAAUAAAUGCUGUAGUUUCAAAUAACAUCCCACCUGUUUGCCUUGUUUGAGGAUCUGGUGAGAUGUAGAAUUCCAGUAGCUUGGCUAAAAAAGGAAGAAAUAAAAGAUAGAAUAACCUGGAAGUUCUCCACUUCCCUUCAGGUAUUUUCUUGUUGUUCUUUAGAUUUGGAAUCUGUUACUGGAUUCUUCUUUCAUCCAUGCUUCAUGGCAUAUAGAUAUGUAGGCAUUAUACAAAAAGCUUAUCUAGCUGGGUGUGGCGGCUCACACCUGUAAUCCUAGCACUUUGGGAGGCCGAGGUAGGAGGAUCGCAUGAGCUCAGGAGUUCAAGACCACCCUAGGCAACAUAGUGAGACCUUAUCUCUACAAAAAAUUAAAAAAUUAGCUGGGUGUGGUUGCCUGCUCUUAUAGUCCCAGCUACUUGGGAGGCUGAGGUGAGAGGAUCGCUUGAGUCCAGGAGUUUGAAGCUGCAGUGAGCUGUGAUUGUGCCACUGCACUCCAGUUUGGGUGACAGAGCAAGACCCUGUCUCCAAAAAAAAAAGAAAGUCUUCACCUAAAAACUUGCAUCUUCUAGAACCAUGAACUAUGGAUGGUCAGACCUUCUUAUUUUUAUGUUAGCAGAUUUUUUUUUCUGUAGAUAAUUUUUCAGCAUUAUGAUUAUAUGACCAACAUGCGAAUGUAAUUUCACAUUUUAGCCUUUGAGUGUCUGCUGGUUCACUCAUCUUAACAGUCUCCAUAUUCUAAAAUUCUGGAGUAGUCCAAGGAACAUUCCUAAGAUUAUUUUGCCAUAUGCUUUGUGCAGAUUUUGAGUCUUUUUCAAUCUUAAGUUUAAAUUGUUUCCAGUUUCUGAAUAUUAAUAAAACAAACAAACCAACCCUCUUAAUGUAUCCCCUGUUCUACACAUUCCCUUACUUUUUGGGAACUCUUUUGUCCCCUGCCCUCACCACCAUCCUACCCUUUGCCAUAUGGAGUGUGGGAUGUAUUGUUUGUUAGGUUUUAAAUAAGCAAAUUUGCCUUCUCUGUGUUGAAGAAACCUUUACUUUUAAAAACUGAUUAUGGCCUCUAGGCACCAAAUCUUAAACAUUUCUGUAGCUUAUCUGUUGAGUUUAUUAUAGAUCGUAUCUAGAAAUUUAUUUAGCUUGUUUGAGUUGCCAACAAAAGUUGGCCAAGAAAUCUGUAUAAUAGAAUUGUCUGUCCAAUUUUGAAAUAUGACUUCUAAUUAUAUCUUUUGCAUACACACAAAAAUCUGCAGUAUUAAUUUGAGCUCUGUCCUAAUCACAAUUAUUUUUUGUUACUUUCCAGUAAAAUAGCUUUUUCUUGUAAAUUUUUGACAUAAACACCAGACCACAUUUAUUAAAAUGAAAAAAUACUUGCUGUUAUCAAGGUAUUCAAAAGUAUUAUAAAAUAUUAAAUAAAGUUAGAGUUUGUGGCACAUUGACUAACAAAUUUUAUCUGACAGAGACCAAGAAAAAAAUACAUAAAAUUAUAAAGUAAAUAAACAAAAUCAGUAAUUUCCACAAACAAGUAUGUUUAUGCAGGAGCACUGUUAACCUACUAGUGUUCAGAGUAAUUUCUGAAUCAAGAUAAUUUCUGAUGGUGCUUUUAAAGAGUCUAGUUAUCUUGUAACUAAUAUGACAUGGGAUUAAAGUUAAUCUCUUUUUAACUACAGUGAGAAAAUUUAAAAGCCUUGGCUUCAUAGACUAAAUACCUGAACAGACAAAUUGCUGAAAUAAUGCAGCUAAGACUGCAAGAGAAACUGCAAAAGAUACCCCAAGUUAUGUUUGUUAUUAAGCAUAGGUUAUUUUGAAAAUAGGUUUCCAUAUGGAGUAUACGGUAUGUAAUUUAUACAGACCACAUUACUAAUAGAUUCUGUCAAGUGGCACUGAAUUCAAGCUACAAUGUCCAUAAUGGAAUAUGUAAGGAAAUUGCUGGUGUUAUUGGGUUGGAUUAAAAGAAAAAAAAAAACACCUUUAUUAGUAUGUGUUCCCCCUCCCCUCAGUGUACACUGCUUCUUGGGCUCAGACUUUGGGGUUUAAGAAUGAGGUAUUUGGGCCGGGCGCGGUUGUUCACGCCUGUAAUCCCAGCAUUUUGGGAGGCUGAGGCGGGUAGAUCACAAGGUCAGGAGAUCGAGACCAUCCUGGCUAACACAAUGAAACCCCAUCUCUACUAAAAAUACAAAAAAUUAGCCAGGUGUGGUGGCAGGUGCCUGUAGCCCCAGCUACUCGGAAGGCUGAGGCACUAGAAUGGUGUGAAUCCGGGAGGCAGAGCUUGCAGUGAGCAGAGAUUGCGCCACUGCACUCCAGCCUGGGUGACAGAAUGAGACUCUGUCUCAAAAAAAAAAAAAAAAAGAUAUUUGAAGGUCUAAUUAUAGGAUAAAUUUGGUGACUAAGAGGUUACUCUUAAUAACAAUAAUCAUAUUUGGUUUACCUAUUUGUCACCAGACAGUAUCCAGACUUCAUGUGACUAAUGGUGACAACUGUAUUUUGAGAAAUUUGGAAAAUCACAUAAGCUGUUGGUGAUACUUUCAAAUCAGAAUGUUUUAAAUAGCGGACAAGGUAAAGCAAGCUCAGAACUUAAUAAUAGAGGAAUAGAUACAGUAUAUUGAAGGAAAAAAAUACAUUGACAUUUGCAAAGAGAAAGAUGCUGUUUCUAUAGCAUACCUAAGUCCAUUGAAUUUGCACAGUGGACAAAUUGCAAUUGGGGAAUAUUAUUCAUAUAAAUAGUCCUGUCAGAACACGGGAUGAGUAGAGUCUUGUGGAACAGUUUGUUUAGAGAAGUACUAGUUAGGAAUCACUUGUAUUAGCUGGUAAGCAUCAAGAGAAACGCUUGGAUAGGGUAGUUUAAUAAACAGUGUCAGCACAUUUACAUGGAUUGUGACAGUUUUAUCUUUUGCUAAAUAGCCUAGAGUAAGCAUUAUUUUAGCAUGUUAUCAAAAAUAAUUAUAAUAUAUUUGGCACCCACUGAAAUUCUGACUUACCUGUUGGGGUAUGUUUUUGGUAAUUCAGAACAGAUUGAUUGAAGAAUCUUCUUUAAAAGUUGCAUUUUAGAUGUUUUCUUUGGGUGGUUCUUGUAGCCAUCACAGAAAUAAACAUACCUUAGUUUGCAAACCGCUAUUUACUUGGAUCUGAAUAGGAAACAUUGUCACGAUGUUACGAUAUACUGUAUUUCCGGAUACCUUAACAAUUAUUAGAUAAACACGAUGAAGAUGGAAAAUAUUGAAGAAAUAAUGAUAUUAUAAAAACUUUUGAAUGGUUUUAGUUGAAAACAAACCAAGAAUAUAUUGGUAUAGACAUAAUUGCAAAGUAGAGCUACCGCACUACCAAAAAAAGUUAUUUGAGGUAGUUGCUGGAAGCAGAAUUUUCACGGUUAGAAAUGCUUAAAAAGAGGCUCUUUUAAGUAGAAAAGAAUGUGAGACUUUAGUUAUUGUAACAGUAGGCUUCAGAGUAGCCAUAAAUGAAGUUUAGCUGGAGUAAGACUAACAGGGUUUUAAUCUGUUGUUUUUCUAGUUAAGGCUUAUUAAUAACAUUUAUGUAUGGCCUUGUUCAUUUGUGCACUGGGACAGAACUAGAACCUUGGGCUCCCCAUUUUGUUCUUUGGUACAGGGCCAUCGUAUUUCAGUAAAUAGAGAGUUUUUUCUCUUCUUAGACGUCUAAACAAUGGCAAUAAUUUAUAACUAACUGCUCUUCGUUAUGUUGCAGAGGCAAAUUGCGCAGAAAAUUAUGGAUAAUUUUAAAAAGAUGAAAUACAGGUGGCUCAUCUAAAACAGACUCCAAUUAAAACCACAUUGUAUUAAAUAGAGCCUGCUUUAGAUAGGCUCCUCUUCAUGCUAAAUAUGAAUGAAGCAACAAUUUUAGAUAUAAUAGCUGGUAUCUGGAUUUUAAUAUGAUCAGUUCUCAUGCUUCGGGGCCCAAAUAUUGCCAGCUGGUAUUAAGAAACCUACCCUCCUAUAAAACUCGAUUAUAUUGUUUUCCCUAAGAGUAUUGCUUUAGGAAUUAUUGAGAAAGUGGUUUUUACAGGGUAUAGACUUUUGCAUAAAAGUUGGUGCUAAAAUUUGACUCAUCAAAAUUUGCAUCACACUCUUGCAUCUGGAAUAUUACCAGAUGGCGUUAAAUUAGACCUUGGGAUGGGUGUCUCAUUCAGAGACAUGGCAGUCUGUACUCAGUGUAAUGGGUGAGCAAAGAUGUGUUCUAGACCUAAGUGUAUGCUGUCUGCAUUAUGGCUUAUAUAAAAUGGCCACAUCUGUUAUUUUAUCAAGAGAAUAAGUUUUCUAAGUUUUGGUUGGUCUGAUAUGCUAAUAUCUGCAAUUAGCAGAGCCUUGACAAAUUGUUCCCUUAAAUUAAGAGUUCAUCAGUUUGGCAGAAUGUGACCUGAUAAAAUGAUUUGGGAAUAUGGUGCUUUUACAUACACAGAUUUUUUUUUUUUCCCGUUUUAGUCUUUCUUAGCCAUCAGACUCCAGAAGAUGUACAAGGCUAUGCCAGUUUUUUUGUUUGUGCUUUUAAAGAAAUUAUUACCGAAUGUGGGGGAUCCACGGAAAGUGAACUCCUGGAGGGACAGAGGAGGAGCAAGACUGUCUGAUCCUGAGAUCUCAGUGCCUAAAACAUAGAAGGGGUUCAGUAAAUACUUGUUUGAAAUAAAAAUAACGAUUAAAAAAAAGGAGGGAAUAGUUCCUACCAUCAUAUGCAAGAUGACAUGGGUAGUCCUGACUCUUCUGGAGUAAGGAGACUGAGCAUUCUCACUGCUGAAUUAGGUGAAGGGAAACUUAGAAUCUCCUUAAAAGGGACAAACAAGACCCUACAUGAUUGGACCUGCCCCUUACCCUGUCUGCCAUUCUUGUCAUUUCUUGCCUCAGCCUUAUUGCCCCAGCAACACAGAUCAGCUGGUAGUUCUUUGCCGAUUUUGUGCUAUUUCCUAUCGUGGAACAUUCUCCCAUGUUGUUCUCCCUAGUCCUUAUCUUGCCUGGUUGGCUACUAAACUUGUAUUUAAGCUUCAUUAUGUUCUGUCUUUUUUUCUGAAGUUGUUCUAAAGCCCUACCUGAGUUGGUGCCUUCUUCUGUUUCUCUGGAAAUCUCUGUGUGUUUCUGCUCUUCUGCACAACGUGAUAAAUUAUUUGAAUUUUCUCCUUCACUAGAUGGUUUUUAUGUCAAGAUGCUUUUCCUUAUAUUUGUUCAAACCCAAACAUUGGACACGAUGGUAGGCCACGGAAAUCAGUUAAUAAGUAUUUGCCAAAUGAUUGUUCAUACCAGCCCUCUCAGUUGCAGAAUGAAAAACUUUGAAUGCUUCUUUAAUAAUAAAUCUUCUUGACUAUUGGCUGUGAUUCUAAGUCCCUUGUUAUAGGAGUAUGGUUAUUAACCUAGUUAUUUCUGCCAUGUUUCAAUGUGGAUAAGCGUAUUUAACAGAUUCGCUCUGUUGCAUUGAUCCUGUGAUGGUGUUAUAUACUACUCCAGUGCCCUGGACUGUGCGCUACAGGGCAGCCUCUAGACUUUGGGAUUAAGUAAUGGUGAUUCGGUGGGGGUAUGGGUUCUUAUUUUAUGGGAGUGUUUUGGCAAUUAAGUGCUAUUUAAAGGUAUUAUUUUUGUUAGAAAGAUAAGGAUUUAGAUCUGUGGUUCAUUAAUUAUGUAAAAGUUGAAUUAGCAAAGGCUAGUUUUUGGCUCAAAUUAUGAAAGAAUACUCUUGGGAAACUGGGUAUCGGGGAGAGGAUAAGUAAGUUUGGUUAUUUGUCUUGAGAUUUUAUAGAGAACACACACGUACCCCAUAAAUGUAGUUUUAAAGAAUUGUUCAAAGUAAAUCAAUUUUUGAUUUUAAGAAAAGCUCCAGGCCGGACAUGGUGGCUCAUGCCUAUAAUCUCACCACCUUGGGAAGCCUAGGUGGGCUGAUCACCUGAGAUCAGGAGUUCGAGACCAGCCUGACCAACGUGGAGAAACCCCGUCUCUACUAAAAAUACAAAAUUAGCUGGGCGUGGUGGCGCAUGCCUGUAAUCCCAGCUACUCGAGAGGCUGAGGCAGGAGAAUCGCUUGAACCCGGGAGGCGGAGGUUGCAGUGAGCCGAGAUCGCACCGUUGCCCUCCAGCCUGGGCAACAAGAGUGAAACUCUGUUUCAAAAAAAGAAACGCUCCACAUUUUUAAAUAAUACACAGGUUUUGCAGUGUAACUACUGGUGAGGACCAGAAAUCUAGUUACUAGAUUUCUUAAAAAUAAAAUUUCUCACACUGUUUAAAAAAAGGAAAAGAAGUACACUUAUUUUUCCUAUGUGUAGUUUAUACAUGCUAAAUAAAUAAAGUUUAGAAAAUGGAAUUUAAGAAGAGUAAAAGCAUCGCCAAUAGUUCCUUCCACACAGGUGUUAAUCAUUUUUUGUUUUCACUUGUCUUUUGUAUUCAUUUUAAAAAUAGAGGACCAUAUUGCGUACACUGCUUUGUAAGCUGCUUUUUGCUUAUCAACAUUUUGUAACUAUCUUUCCAUGUUAUUAAUAACUGAGUUUUAAUGCUUUUAUCAUAAUUUAAUCAUAAUUUUGGCUCAGCCAUAUUAGCUCUUUCUUGAUAGAUUUUACUGUGUAAUUUAAUAAUCCAGUUUUGGACUUUUCCCACUUAGACUAGUAUUCUUUAUUAGAUUUAACAUGAACUAAGUGCUAUAAAUGAGUCAAUAUUUUUUUAAAAUUAUAUGUCUGUUUAUCAGUGUACUGUUUCAAGUCUAUGUAUUAGUUAAGUCUGUUCUUCAGGCUUGAACAUAGGCAUACCUCCUUUUAUUGCACUUGGCUUUACUGCACUCUGCAGAUACUGCAUUUCUUUUACAAAUUGAAGCAGUGGCAGAGUUUGAAAGAAUUGACUCCAAUUUUGAAAGAAGUCCUAGUGUGGAUAACAUGCUAUCCAAAGCAUCAAUGCUACAGAGAAAUCUUUUCUGAAUGGAAGAGUCAAUUGAUGCGGCAAACCGUCUAUUUUAUGAGUAGACACCACAGCCACCCGUCUUCAUCAACCACCACCCUGAUCAAUCAGCAGCCAUCAACAUCUAGGCAAGACCCUCUGCCAGCAAAAAGAUUACACCUCACUGAAGGCUCAGACGAUUGUUAGCAUUUUUUAGCAAUAAAGUAUUUUAGAUGUAUGUAUGCUGUUUUUUUUAGACAUAAUGCUAUUGCACACUUAAUAGACUACAGCAUCGAAUAAACAAAUUUUAUAUGCACUGGGAAACCAAAAAAAAAUCAUGUGACUUGGUUUAUGUGGUGGUUUGGAGUGGAACCUGAGUUCGUCCGAUGUUUGCCUGCAGAUGCUCAUCCUUUACUCUUUCCCCACUACUGUUGGUGCUCCCAGUUCUGCUGUCUGCCUUUAUCCAAUUGUAAGCCUCAAUGUGAUUUCUAGAUUCACCCUAAGUACUUGCCCUUGAUCAGCCCAGCACUGAACUCCCCCAAACACACAAACAUUAAAGUUCAUUUAGAAAGAGUGAAUUUUAGGAAGAAACCACAGAGGCCAAGAUCUUCUCUAAUUAAUGUAGUGAAUCUUCUGAAUGUAGUGAGUCUUCUGGCCAUUUUUUGAGUAUUACAUUGAUAGCUCAUUCAAAACGAAAAUUAUUCACACAACUAUGGUGUAAAUAAAAAGAUGUGAUGUUAAUAUAAUUUUUGGAUUAGAUUAUUGCCGAAUCAAGCAUCUUUACAACAUUAUAGUUUAGAGUAAUGUGUUUGGCUAAAUUAGGCAAUAAAAGUAAACAUAAAAGGUAAACCUUCCCGAUUAGUCCUUACAUUUGACUUCUCUGUAUGUGAAACACUGACAAAAACCAAAAAUAAUUUCACUACUCUGUAUUUAUUUUUCUGAUUGAGACUUUGGAAAAGUCAAGAAUGACAACGGUAGGUAUUUCUUUUUUGCAGAACAAGCCUGAGAUGGUACUUAGGUGCUUACAUACAAGCUACUGAUCACUUAAUGACAUUAAAAAAAUUUUAAUUACUUAUUGCCUUCAGACACUACAGAAGUUUAAAAAUCCUACUAUUUCCACUUAAAUUUCUAGACCAAUGCUGUUGGACUUUCUUUCCCUUUAACAGCAAUGAUUAUCCAGUUGAAUGUUGUUUCACAGAAAGGAAAAGUGCAUUUGUGUAAAAAUAUCUGGGGCUUGCCAGGGAAUCUUUUUCAGAAUGCUUUGUGGUUACAAAUGAAGCUUAUUGUUGUAUAAAUGGCAAGUUUAAAAUCAUAGAACUUUUUUGCAGUAGCUCAUGGCAUGAGUUGAUAAUCUGCGAAUUGCUCUGCGUGUGUGUUUGUGUGUGUUCGCAUGCAUGCCUCAGCCCAUCUGUAAGUAGCUGGAUCCUGUGCCGUUCCUCCCCCUGUUUCCCACCUCACUUAUUUAGAUACAUAAAUACGCACACUUUUACAUCUAAGGCAAACCCCAAAAGAUGCAUGUGGAAGGCUGGAUGUGGGAGAGAGGUGUUUUCCUUUAAUUGACCUCUCACGGCGUUCCACUUGAUAAAGUGACAACAUUUUCUGAAAACUUAAGGUUUUUGAAUGUGUGGAUUUUCUCCCUACCACUGUAAUUUCUGAAACUUUCUCUAAACAAGAUGGCUGGCACAUUAUGGGGACAGAGCAGAGACAUAGAACAGAGACAAAGCCGCCCUGAGAAGGCAGACACACUUAUAUUGCUUGUGGUUUUUCAGUACAGCUGCUUUCAGAUGAGCCGGCUUGUUCUAAGCUGGUCCCACUGCCAAAGCAAGACUGUCACACAGCUGGUAGUACUUACUGUACUUGCGGGAAAGUAUGUGAUUCAUUAGUUGGAACCGUAUGUUUUUCACCAGUUCUGGUCAUGUUUUUGUUAGGAUGUGGUAAAAACACAAGCAGGGGGUGAAGGGACAAUGGAAACAUGUGACUUCUUAAGGAUUGGCCUGAACCCGUUAUUAGCUAAAUUGUACACCGUAAAAUGUCCUUUGUACCUCAUAAGACAAAUGACUUAAUUUUUUAUUCCUCAGUUGAGGUCAUUCAGUCAUAAGUGGUAAAAAUUAUCAACACUGAGCUCUUUUUCUCUUUUUACUUUCUGCAAAGUAUUAUGAUCCGUUUAAACCCCAAAUUAUAAUAUGAAGGGAAGUCAUGCAAGUAAAAGACAUUAAUUUGCUGAAAAAUGCCCAUGACGGGUGAAGAACUUUAACUGGAGUGAACUCUUGCUACUGAUAAAAUAUGAGUAUGGUAUUACAGCUCAUAAGAAACACUUCUAAUACCACAGGGUGUGAGGAGAACAAUAAAUGGGAGUUUCUUUGUCUACACAUGAUCAAGCAGACUCAAAUUGUAUGGCUGGAGGAUUGAGAGACUAGUCUUUUAAGUAAUUUUGGUGUCAUUAAUGGGCUUGCAUCACAGUAUCUCUGUAAUGCUCAAUCCUGGUAUUGUGCAGAACUGCUGGUGUGAGCCGCAUUGAAUAUUGGCCUGUUAUCACCAGGUUUUUGAGCUUGUGAAUAUUUUACAACUGCACAGGCCGAACCAUAUUCUUUGGAAAAUGAAUGCCAUUGCUGCUGUGUUGUGUUCUCCUUACAUAGGAAUAUGCUUUGACAUUUGCUUGCUUCUGCUUCAUUCUGACACUGGAGUUGUUUUACUUUUGUCCCCACUCCCAUAGCCUGCUAUUGAGACAGGUGGUAUUUUCAAAGUCUAAGUAAAAUAUUGGCAGAUUAUGCCUCUACCCUCAGACUCUGUUUUUCAACUGUUCCCUUCUAAAGUUCUGCACCGUUCAUGCCUCACUACAUACACUCCAGCAGUUGCUGGACUCUGCAGAAUUAGAACCAGGUCUGUCUCUGACAAUUAGCUCAACUGGCUGCAGGAUAAAUAAAGGAAUGCGCUCAGGGGCUGUAGUCUGUGACACAGUGUAACAGAGCGUAAAAAGGUGCAUCUGUUCCAUGCCCUGAUUCAGUCGCCUCACUGUCACUGGGAAGUUACCGACACGGAGACAUGCCCGUGCUGUUUGGUAAACAAGCGGCAGGUAUUAAAUUAACAGGGCUGUGAGUGUGCAAACGUGCUGCUUUAUUAAAAGCCCUGCUAUCUUGGCUCACUGCUGGGUCACAGGCAGUUGCUAGAGCAUCUAGUAAGAUGACUCAUGGCACUGCAUACUUCAAUACCCUGUUCUCGCUUCCUUCCAGAGGGGACCGUUGACAUUUGAGAGCCUGAUUACGGAAGGAAAAAAAGGAGAAAGAAAAGAGAAUACAGGGUGUGUGUGUGUGUGUGUGUGUUUGCCUUUUACGUUUCGUAGGCUAGGCAAGAAGGAGAUGAGGGCCAGCACCCCAGAGCCAGGUUUUAGUUUAAAUUGGGCUUCUGAAUCCAAUACUAAAUUGCAACCAGGUCUCUGUCUUUGUUGUUGUUUAUUUUCUCUGCCUUUCUGUCUCACCCUCCUCAUGACUGCUACUUGAUUUGUGGUUGAAAUAAUGAGGGGAUAACUGAGAGAUGAAAGUUUUGCUCUGUCUGCCUGCACUGGGUGGGCACCAUGCAUCUUGCAAAUGUACUUGCAGGAAAAAACACUUCGACUUUUAUUAUAUUCUUUAAGCAUUUAUCGCCUUUGCAUUUAAUAUUUUUAAUGAAAAACUCGCAUUUUAAAGACUUUCUGCUUUCAUUCAGCAAUGUCAUGAUUUUUGAAGUUUGUUUUCCCUUCAGCUUCAGGAAUGCUUUACACAGGGUCAUGUGUGGUUGCCUUGUUGAAUUGUUCCUCACUUUUGUGGUCUUAUCUUUGAGGAGUCCUCUUUAGAUAUACCAAGGUCUGUAGGCAAACAUUACAAGACAAUUUUCAGUACACAUGUCUGUGCUAAAGAGACUGGCAUUUCUGAAGGUUUCCUGCUCCCCUCCAAGUUGUGUUUCUUUUAAGGGCCCCAACUAGCUCCUCAUCCAUUAGAAGAUGAUGUAAUGCUAAUGGUAUCUAGCUCCACACAGCUUGGACCAAAAAUGAUUCCAGUUGGCUGUAUUUGAAUGUGAAUGACCAGAAGGUGCUAGACAUUCUCCACUGUAAUUGCAAGUGCUUACCUUGGAAAUCUCUUUUGGUUGUAGAGGUCCUUUGGUCCUCAUACUAGAGAUCAUACCGCCACACAUGCAUUCCUACUGUCCAGACCCAUCUUUAUUGUUGGCUGUCUUUUUAUAGUGAUGUCUAGGUAGAGGAGUGCGAUGCCCAGGGUCGGGGAUAGGGAGGGUGGAGAGGAAGCAGCCUUUCUCAUUGUUUGCUCAGAAAGGAAAGUAUCCCACUAUCUAGAGAGUUAGUGAUGCCUCAGAAUCUCUUUAUCUUUGUAACCUCUUUUCUGUAUGAAGUUUAAUAAGCCGGCUGUGCAGUUUUUAAAACGCCAGUGGAUUCCGCUUUUCACUUGGACCGCCCCCCGCCUUUUGCUCUGAGCAUUCACUCCCUGUUUCCUUAUUUCCCCCGUUCUCUUUUCCUUUAUCUCAGGGGAGUUCCCUGAGUAGCAAGACUGAAAAAGAGCUGAGGUUUAUGUUAGAAGAAAUUAAGGUUAAUGAUCAUUGGCUCAUUUUCAUAUUCUGUGGGUGUGGAUGGAGGAGUAAUCAGUGCAGGUGGCCCUGCCAGUUGGGAGUUUUUCUUUGUCAUCAAGAAAAUAAGGAGAGUGCAGGGAUUGAAUUACCACAACUAUUUCAGGACUAAACAUAUUUCAUUUCCCGAUCGGGUCUGGUUUAAGGACGCAAAGCUGACAUUAAUUUUAUCCAAAGAAAGCACAGCAUUUUUUUUGUUUCAUAAUUUGACUAAUGCAUAGGGUAGAUGCAUGUUCAAAUUUAAUUCUAGUAUAAUCUUACAAAUAAUUCUCUGAAAAGCAAAGGGGUUUUGAUUCAGUUUGACAGUUUAUGUUUCUGUGUCCAAUUACCACUUAGUUAUUGAAUGUUAAAAAGCUGCUUUCUAAAAUGUGCACUCCGACUGCACCAAUUGGCUUCCCAGCUGCCUGCUAUUACAUGCGAGGUGCUCUCUUCUAACUUUUUAAAGGAUGUACACAGUUGAAGUAGUUAUGUUUAGCUAGCAAAGGAAGUGGGGGAUUUGGUUAGGAAGUGCUUGCUGGCCUUGAAAAACUAUCAUGUGUGCAUUCUCAUUUCAGCCACAUAAAGAUCAUUCUUUAAAUAAAUACUUGUUGGAUUAAAAAAACCUUAAAUGCUCCGAUAAACUAGAGAAAUAACUUUGAUUUUUUUUAAAAACAUGACUUCCAUUUGGAUCAACUUUUUAAAGUUUUCAAUAUGCUUUUAAUACCACUGAUGUAACUUUCUACAAGUGAGGUAUUCUGAUUCCAUGCUUGGAAAAAGAAGAUCUACAGGUUGACCAGAGACAAUAAAAGUCAUUGAGGAAGAGUGUCAACACUUGCCAUGCAUGGCCAUCCGUUGCACACUGGUAAACUGCACAUGUGAAUGUUUUCAGCCAGGGAAGAUUAACCUGAGGACUUGUGAUCAGUGUAAACAUGGCUGGGUGGCACAUGCCUUGGAUAAGCUCAGCACGCAGCACCUGUACCACCCCACCCAAGUGGAGAUUGUGCAGUCCAACGUCGUGUUUGACAUCAGCAGCCUGAUGCUCUAUGGGACACAAGCAGUGCCUGUGCGGCUAAAGAUCCUGCUGGACCGUCUCUUCAGCGUCCUGAAGCAAGAGGAGGUACUGCACAUACUGCACGGCCUUGGCUGGACUCUGCGGGACUAUGUCCGAGGAUACAUCCUUCAGGAUGCUGCUGGCAAGGUGCUGGACCGCUGGGCCAUCAUGUCUCGAGAAGAGGAAAUCAUCACCCUUCAGCAGUUUCUGCGGUUUGGAGAAACCAAAUCCAUUGUGGAGCUGAUGGCAAUUCAGGAGAAAGAAGGGCAGGCCGUGGCUGUACCAUCUUCAAAGACAGACUCAGAUAUAAGGACUUUCAUUGAGAGCAAUAAUCGCACCAGGAGUCCCAGCCUCCUUGCUCACUUAGAGAACAGCAAUCCUUCCAGCAUUCAUCACUUCGAAAACAUCCCAAACAGCCUUGCAUUUCUGCUUCCAUUCCAGUACAUAAACCCUGUCUCAGCACCACUGCUAGGGUUGCCUCCAAAUGGGCUACUGUUAGAGCAACCAGGGUUGAGGCUGCGGGAACCCAGCCUUUCAACUCAGAAUGAAUAUAAUGAGAGCAGCGAAUCCGAAGUUUCUCCCACACCUUAUAAGAAUGAUCAAACACCCAAUAGAAAUGCCCUGACCAGCAUUACUAAUGUGGAGCCCAAAACCGAGCCAGCCUGUGUCUCUCCCAUUCAGAAUUCUGCCCCAGUCAGUGAUCUAACCAAAACUGAACACCCAAAAAGCUCAUUCCGGAUUCAUCGGAUGAGAAGGAUGGGGUCAGCCUCUAGGAAAGGAAGAGUGUUCUGUAAUGCAUGUGGGAAGACAUUCUAUGACAAAGGUACUCUCAAAAUUCAUUACAAUGCUGUUCACCUGAAGAUCAAACAUCGAUGCACCAUUGAAGGUUGCAACAUGGUCUUUAGCUCCCUCCGAAGUCGUAAUCGCCACAGUGCAAACCCCAAUCCUCGCCUUCACAUGCCUAUGCUAAGGAAUAACCGAGAUAAAGAUUUAAUUCGGGCCACCUCAGGAGCUGCCACCCCUGUCAUAGCAAGUACAAAAUCAAAUCUGGCACUCACAAGCCCUGGCCGACCCCCAAUGGGUUUUACCACUCCCCCUCUAGACCCUGUCUUGCAAAAUCCUCUCCCUAGCCAGCUAGUAUUUUCUGGGCUAAAGACUGUACAACCAGUUCCUCCAUUUUAUAGAAGUUUACUCACUCCAGGGGAAAUGGUGAGUCCUCCAACCUCCCUCCCAACCAGUCCCAUCAUUCCAACCAGUGGUACCAUAGAGCAGCACCCCCCGCCACCCUCUGAGCCAGUAGUGCCAGCAGUGAUGAUGGCCACCCAUGAGCCCAGUGCUGACCUGGCACCCAAGAAAAAGCCCAGGAAGUCAAGCAUGCCUGUGAAGAUUGAGAAGGAAAUUAUUGAUACCGCCGAUGAGUUUGAUGAUGAAGAUGAUGACCCCAAUGAUGGUGGAGCUGUGGUCAAUGACAUGAGCCAUGACAAUCAUUGUCACUCCCAAGAGGAGAUGAGCCCAGGCAUGUCUGUGAAGGACUUUUCUAAGCAUAACAGGACCCGGUGCAUUUCAAGGACUGAAAUAAGGAGGGCCGACAGCAUGACUUCUGAAGACCAAGAACCUGAGCGGGACUAUGAGAACGAGUCUGAGUCUUCGGAGCCCAAACUGGGCGAGGAAUCCAUGGAAGGGGAUGAGCACAUUCACAGCGAAGUGAGUGAAAAAGUCCUGAUGAAUAGUGAGAGGCCUGAUGAGAACCACAGUGAGCCCUCUCACCAGGACGUCAUCAAGGUGAAGGAAGAAUUUACAGACCCCACUUACGACAUGUUUUACAUGAGCCAGUAUGGACUGUACAAUGGUGGGGGUGCCAGCAUGGCCGCCUUGCAUGAGAGCUUUACAUCGUCUCUGAAUUAUGGCAGCCCUCAAAAGUUCUCCCCAGAAGGUGACCUAUGUUCUAGCCCAGACCCCAAAAUCUGUUAUGUGUGCAAGAAGAGUUUCAAAAGCUCCUACAGUGUGAAACUUCACUACAGGAACGUUCACUUGAAAGAGAUGCACGUCUGCACAGUGGCUGGUUGCAAUGCUGCAUUCCCCUCUCGCCGAAGCCGAGACAGAAACAGAAAUUUACGGAUGGAAAGAACCAUAGGUCCAGGACAUCGAGACAGCCUGCAUCUCCGAAGAGGAAAUUCUAACCGGCCUGGAACCUGCUGUCUUCAUACGGGAGAUUCUCUUGAAGAGAGCGUGAUAGUCAGAAUUAGCUGUGCCAACAUAAACCUACAUCGUAAACUGUUGACCAAAGAACUCGAUGACAUGGGCCUGGACUCGUCGCAGCCCUCCCUUAGCAAGGACCUCCGCGAUGAAUUUUUGGUGAAGAUAUAUGGUGCCCAGCACCCCAUGGGGCUCGAUGUCAGGGAAGACGCCUCCUCUCCCGCAGGGACUGAAGACUCCCACCUGAACGGGUAUGGGAGAGGCAUGGCAGAGGACUACAUGGUCCUUGACUUGAGCACCACCUCCAGCCUCCAGUCCAGCAGCAGUAUCCAUUCCUCCAGAGAAUCCGACGCAGGCAGCGAUGAGGGGAUUCUUCUCGAUGACAUUGACGGGGCGAGUGACAGUGGGGAGUCGGCACACAAGGCCGAGGCCCCUGCCCUCCCUGGCAGCCUAGGGGCUGAAGUUUCAGGAUCUCUUAUGUUCAGCAGCUUGUCUGGGAGCAAUGGUGGGAUCAUGUGCAACAUUUGCCACAAAAUGUACAGCAACAAGGGGACCCUGAGAGUGCACUACAAAACUGUGCAUUUGAGAGAAAUGCACAAGUGCAAAGUCCCAGGUUGCAAUAUGAUGUUUUCCUCUGUACGAAGCCGAAAUCGGCACAGUCAGAACCCUAAUCUCCACAAAAACAUUCCCUUCACUUCAGUAGAUUAGUCUCAGAAUGGACACUACAAAUGCCAGCUCUCACCAGAUGGCCUACGUGUUUGAACUGCCAUAGUCAGUGUGCGCUUAUGUACUUGGGGUGUGUGUGUGUGUGUGUGUGUGUGUGCAUUUAUGUAUGCUCUGUGGCUACAUAUACACACACGUAUUUCCUUGAGAUAAACAAGAUAAACACUAGGUGCUUUUGAAUUUUUUUCACUUCCCUUUAUAGUUUUGGGAAAGGAGUGGGAUCUUUGAUUUCAGGGUGAAAACAGAGUACCCCUUUAAACACACACACACACACAUGCACAUACACACACACACACACACACACACACAGUGUGCAACUAGCCCCAGUUUUGACAGAAUAAUUCUUGGUCUUCCCCAAAGAGACAAUUUGUUGUACCCAUGACUGUUGCCUGCAAAAAUAAAAGGGAAAAAAAAGAAAAAAGAAACAAAAAGGAACUUCUUAUAGUUGUCUUUUGUGAACUUUAAGGUUUUGAAAGAAUCUUCAAUUAAAGCAUGGCAGAUUCACCUGUAAAUAUUUAGCCUUGAGGGGCCAUUGAUGUAAAACAAUUGUAUUGAUGGUUGUUUAACUUUUUUGUUUAAUUUUUACAGUUACAUCCAGCUGUUAGAUAUGCAGGAAAAGAUAGUUUGCUGGCUAGCUCUAUUCAUUUAUGUUAGCAUUAAUGCACAUUUUUAAAAAAAGAAAAAAACAUGGUCUUGUUUUUACUACCUGUUAGAUAUAGUGCUAAAGAGGUGCUGGCAUGCUUUACAGCACAGAUCUGAUUUUUUAAAAUGUCCUGUACUAGUACAUAAAUCCCGUCAUGCACUUUUUUUCAUACACUACAAGGGGAUGUGUAAUAACCAUGCUUCUUUUUUAUCCUUAAACUAUUGCCAUACUUCAGUAAGUGUCUUUUUUAAAAAAAAUUCACUUGUAUAAAAAUGGUCUGGUCAGUAUAGGGCACAAAUGCCAAACAAAGUAUUAGUGUUAACACAAAACUGCCAACUUUGCACAAGUUUCCAGAAAAGAAAAUACAAUUAGUCACUCAACAUAACCACAGGCCAAUUUGUUGGCCACCAGAAAACCGCUUUUUAAAAAAACACUUGGUGAUUCUUUCAAGUGCCGAAUGUUAUUAGAAUCAACAUUGCAUCCUUCUUGCUUAUACGUUAAGUUACAUAAAAGGAAAACAAAAUUAUGUGGUGUGAAACAGCCAAGGCAUUUAUUCUUCAGAGGCAGGAUAAUAUUUCAGGAUACAAAAGCCCAAAUUACCCGCUACGGAACAAAGAUGAAUACAGUAAAAGAGUCGAACACUCAUUUCCAAGGCCCUAACCCUUAUCCUUUAAAAAGAAAUCCUCUGAACUGGGUCGGUCUGUUGUAUGGCUGUCUAAUUUGUUGCAAAUUCUGCAGUCGUACUAUAAUUCAGGCCUGUUUGGUAGACAAAAUCAAAAGGCAUUUAACAGCAGCAGUACUUGGAAGCUUUGAAAACAUGUGCUAAACUUGAAUGGAGCAACACUCCUUUCUGAAAAGCCAGAAGAAGGGGGUUUUAAAGCAGGAUCUCUCAAUGUUCAGUGUUUUGUGUUUCCCCACACGAUUUGUCAGAGAGAAAUGAAAGCAAGCCUGAAACCAAGCAAUUGAGAGUGAGAAAGAGGAGAGAGACUAUUCUCCAAACCUUUUUUGUUUUGUUUUGUUUCCGAUGUUUACACAUGUUGCCUGAGCUGGUUAACCACAUCGGCAGCCUCAGCUACCACAACAUACUGACUAAAUGAUGAUAUUUACUCAAGUUCAGUCUGCAGCCAAAACCAUUAGGGUGUGCAUUGCAGACUGUUUUGUUGUCUUUUUUUUUUCUUUUUUCCUUUUUUUUUAAGUGGAGGGGAAAAGAAGAGAUAAACAAGGAAUAUUUUGUCAAACAGUACACAAUAAUUUAAAGAGAAUGUAUUUCUUUUUUGCAUUUAAUGGCCUCAGACAUUUCUUUCAUCAGUCUAAAAGUUAGAAAUAUCCCUUUAUUUUAACUUUUAUGUCGUUUCCAUUUUUCAUGUUUUUGUAAUUAUUUUUUCUAUGUUCACAUCAGCAUUCACUUCCGUUAAAUUUGCCAAAGGAAACUGUUAAUAUGUUUCUGUUGUUAUUAUUCCUGUAGGAUUUAUUGUACCUCACAGUAUUUAUUGUUUCCCAAAAUAAGCAUCAUUAGUUGGGGAUUCAGUAUUUUUGUUGUGAAAAUUUCAGAAACAAUAGAUUCUUAAAGAUAAGCUAGCUAUGUCUAGGAGCUUUAUCUUUUCACCUCCUUCAGAGGAUGCUAUGGGGUCCAUUUUAAUUCUUCAUUUGUUCUACGGGGAGGAAAGACCAAAAGUAUUUGCAGUACAAAAGAAACUAUAUCAAACACUAUGUUAAAUGACAAGUGUUUAUGGUAAAAAGCUGAGGAAUUAGUAAUAAUCGUUUUUGUUUUCUUGUACUUUGAAUUCCCCAAAGUCUUAAUUGCUUUAUUUUGGUGUUGUGUUAAAUUGAACAGACAGAUGUUUUCCUUUGUUUUAUACCAUAUAAGACUCUGUACAGUAUGUUUGUGAAAGAUUGAACUAGAAUAAUGAAAGUUUGUUUGCAAACA